AGUAAUAUUUAAUUUGUCGGAGACCACAAACCAACCUUGAGCUGGGAGGUACGUGCUCUUCUUGACAGACGUUGGAAGAAGACCUGGCCUAAAGAGGUCUCUUUUGGUGGUCCUUUUCAAAGUCUUCACCUGAGCCCUGCUCUCCAGCGAGGCGCACUCCUGGCUUUUGCGCUCCAAAGAAGAGGUGGGAUAGUUGGAGGUGAGUUUCACCCUGGAGGACUGAGGGGGGAAAUAGGUUUCUCUUUGCACUUGGCCCUCCUUGGCUUUUCACCCCGUCUUAGUCUUGCUGAAUCUUCUCUUGCUGUGCUGCUACUUCUCAUGAACGAAAUAAGAAUGGCUUCGUGUGUCACCUGGCAAGAAUGGAUUCUCUCGAAAGGUUUGAAAAUCCCUAUUUUGCUUGGUGGCCCAGACCAUCUGUGCUCAAUGAGCUAAGCAAAUCUGGCUGGGCUAUUACCUGGGAGAGUCCAGAUUUUUCCUCUCUGGAGGGGCCUGAAGAUUAUUUAUGGGAAUUAAUUUUAUCCCCAAAUCUCUGAGAACUUAAAGGGAUUGGGAAGGUCUUUCUGGAUUUCCCUUUCCCUCUACUGGAGAUGUAGCGGUUCAGCCUUCUUCCGAUGCCAUGUUUGUUUUUCGUGUCUUCGGCCUAGGGUCGCCUUGCCAGCAAGCCUAAAGGCCUCCAAGCUGACUUGGAGGGUGAGGGUGUUUUCACAAAUAAAUACAUCGCCUGGGCAAAGGGAAAAUAUCUGUUUGCAAACAAACCUGGAAGGUGGAGUGAGCACCAUAGCAAAGGAGGGCUGGCUUUCUCCCCGGUUGCCCCACAUUCAGGGUUGGAGAUUCUCCACUUUGGCAUUUUGCAGCAAUGGCCUGGCCUGGGAUUUUAGCAGAGCAGUCACAGAGGGUUACACAGCUGCUGACCUCGGGGCAUUUCUCCUCCCUCCAUCCCUUUCUCCAGACCUUGACUUGCAGGCCCAAGUCUCUUAUCAGAACCCUAGAAAAAUCAGUAUGAUGGGGGUACAGGAGGUAAGGAUGGGAAACAGAACAGGACUCCUGACAUUUACUCCAAGCACCAAUAUUCGGUGUCCCAAUCUGGGUCUGCUCAGACUGAGACCUACUGACUGUGUUUGUGCUUUUAUUGACCUCUUCAACUCACCCUAAAAAAAAAAAAUACAUCUCAGAGAGGGAAAGGGCAAGGAGAGGAGACCAGUGGAGAUGAAAACCCUAGCCAGUCCCCAGUGACUGUUUGAUUAUUUUAAUAAAACUGGGCACUGCCUUGUGUACACCUGGAGCAGGGGACGUCUGGUGGCCCCACUGGGUGGGGGGUGAGGGCCCGCAGCGAUUUCUUAGCAUCUUUGAUCUCGGCCCCCAUCCCAAUGCACCUUCACCCUGCCUUCACCCCAGAGUCGUUGAGAGUAGGGGUGAUGAGUAGGGGGUGGAGGGGAGAUGUCAGGAAGGCGAGCGCCGGCCAGGCGGGGUCAGGCAGCUCUCCUUCUCGAGGUCAGCGUUGGAGAGAAUGUCUGCAAGGCUGCGGAGGCCCGCGGUGUGUUUGUGUGUGUGCGUCCAGACUCGGUUCUCUGCACCGCCAGCGUCACUGAGAUUACUUCCCGAUUAGAAGCCGACCGCGUUUGAAAUGAUUUGUGCAGGAGUUUUUGCAGCCACCGCUUGCUCAGAGAAGCAGAGAUGGAUGGAGAGCAGAACCUUGCGCGGGCACAGGGCCCUGGGCGCACCAUGGCCGACGCAGACGAGGGCUUUGGCCUGGCGCACACGCCUCUGGAGCCUGACGCAAAAGACCUGCCCUGCGAUUCGAAACCCGAGAGCGCGCUCGGGGCCCCCAGCAAGUCCCCGUCGUCCCCGCAGGCCGCCUUCACCCAGCAGGGCAUGGAGGGAAUCAAAGUGUUUCUCCAUGAAAGAGAACUGUGGCUAAAAUUCCACGAAGUGGGCACGGAAAUGAUCAUAACCAAGGCUGGAAGGCGGAUGUUUCCCAGUUACAAAGUGAAGGUGACGGGCCUUAAUCCCAAAACGAAGUACAUUCUUCUCAUGGACAUUGUACCUGCCGACGAUCACAGAUACAAAUUCGCAGAUAAUAAAUGGUCUGUGACGGGCAAAGCUGAGCCCGCCAUGCCUGGCCGCCUGUACGUGCACCCAGACUCCCCCGCCACCGGGGCGCAUUGGAUGAGGCAGCUCGUCUCCUUCCAGAAACUCAAGCUCACCAACAACCACCUGGACCCAUUUGGGCAUAUUAUUCUAAAUUCCAUGCACAAAUACCAGCCUAGAUUACACAUCGUGAAAGCGGAUGAAAAUAAUGGAUUUGGCUCAAAAAAUACAGCGUUCUGCACUCACGUCUUUCCUGAGACUGCGUUUAUAGCAGUGACUUCCUACCAGAACCACAAGAUCACGCAAUUAAAGAUUGAGAAUAAUCCCUUUGCCAAAGGAUUUCGGGGCAGUGAUGACAUGGAGCUGCACAGAAUGUCAAGAAUGCAAAGUAAAGAAUAUCCCGUGGUCCCCAGGAGCACCGUGAGGCAAAAAGUGGCCUCCAACCACAGUCCUUUCAGCAGCGAGUCUCGAGCUCUCUCCACCUCAUCCAAUUUGGGGUCCCAAUACCAGUGUGAGAAUGGUGUUUCCGGCCCCUCCCAGGACCUCCUGCCUCCACCCAACCCAUACCCACUGCCCCAGGAGCAUAGCCAAAUUUACCAUUGUACCAAGAGGAAAGAGGAAGAAUGUUCCACCACAGACCAUCCCUAUAAGAAGCCCUACAUGGAGACAUCACCCAGUGAAGAAGAUUCCUUCUACCGCUCUAGCUAUCCACAGCAGCAGGGCCUGGGUGCCUCCUACAGGACAGAGUCGGCACAGCGGCAAGCUUGCAUGUAUGCCAGCUCUGCGCCCCCCAGCGAGCCUGUGCCCAGCCUAGAGGACAUCAGCUGCAACACGUGGCCAAGCAUGCCUUCCUACAGCAGCUGCACCGUCACCACCGUGCAGCCCAUGGACAGGCUACCCUACCAGCACUUCUCCGCUCACUUCACCUCGGGGCCCCUGGUCCCUCGGCUGGCUGGCAUGGCCAACCAUGGCUCCCCACAGCUGGGAGAGGGAAUGUUCCAGCACCAGACCUCCGUGGCCCACCAGCCUGUGGUCAGGCAGUGUGGGCCUCAGACUGGCCUGCAGUCCCCUGGCACCCUUCAGCCCCCUGAGUUCCUCUACUCUCAUGGCGUGCCAAGGACUCUAUCCCCUCAUCAGUACCACUCUGUGCACGGAGUUGGCAUGGUGCCAGAGUGGAGCGACAAUAGCUAAAGUGAGGCCUGCUUCACAACAGACAUUUCCUAGAGAAAGAGAGAGAGAGAGGAGAAAGAGAGAGAAGGAGAGAGACAGUAGCCAAGAGAACCCCACGGACAAGAUUUUUCAUUUCACCCAAUGUUCACAUCUGCACUCAAGGUCGCUGGAUGCUGAUCUAAUCAGUAGCUUGAAACCACAAUUUUAAAAAUGUGACUUUCUUGUUUUGUCUCAAAACUUAAAAAAACAAACACAAAAAGAUGAGUCCCACCCCCCACUACCACCACACCCAUCAACCAGCCACAUUCACGCUACUCCCCAGAUCUCUUCCCCCAUUCCUUCUUUUGGGCUCUAGAAAGUCUUGCCUCAUUGAGUGUUUUUCCCUAGUGCGUAGUUGGAGUCUGUCCCUGUCUUGGUGUUAAUGUUGACAUUGUUAUAUAAUAAAUGAUAAUAUAUUUUUUUCUUUCAAUUUUCUUAAUGGGACCCAGUCCCUUAUUUGGGGGGAGGUCUGAGGCAAGUAUAUUUCAAAAUAUGUACUUGCGGGAUUCCCUUCAAGUAAACCAUCCCUGAAACCUAAAUUCACGUUUCCCCUUGACUAAGAAAAGCACCUACCUCUGCCAUGUGAUGUUUCUGAAAAGCCUCUGUAUGUCCCCAUUUGCUUUGGUUUUGUCCUGCCUUCUCCAAUAUCACGUGCUCAGUUUUGCCUCUACUUACCCAUGGAGUCAGGAUAACACUGACGCUCCCUGGCAUCCUAUCUUAUUCAGCCCUACCAUCUUGCCAGCUCUGUCUUUCCAGCUGUCUGUCGCUAAAACGUGGCCUAUAGCUUCCCUUCCGGAAAGCUUGCUUUGAAAAACUUAAAAAGCCCCCGUUUACAUGUAGGCAGGACUGUGAUAACAGUGCAAGCUCUGUGUUGACAAGAGUUGUGGACAAAAAGCCAAAAUAAAUAUUCUUCCUGAUUAAAAAAAUUUUUUUUGAAAAAAACAAGGCCAGCCCCAACCUUCCAAACCUCCAUCACCAACAACCCAAACUGGAUGUCAAGCAAAAUGCACAAUUCCUACAGAAGAGGCAAGACACAGUCACCAAUGAUAUCUCGCCAAAGAAACCACGCCCACACCAAUGCCAACACAAAACUGUGUUUACUGAAAGCCGAAAACAGUAUUAAAAAAAGUGUGUAAGUAAAGUGUUAUGGUAGGGUUCUUCAGAUGUAAUAUUUUACUGGUACUAUUUAUUUAUAAAUAGGAAUUCUAAUUAAGUAAUAACAUGAAAUGAAACCCAGCAUAGGAGCUGGCCAAGAGCUUUUAAUUUUAUUGAUACUCAAAACCAAGUUUGUGUUUUUUUGUUUUUUUUUGUUUUUUUCCUCUUUCGAAUGUGCUUUGCUUUUUUUGAUUAAAAAGAAUUUUUUUUUUCCUUUUUUAUAAACAGACCCUAAUAAAGAGAACAGGGUAAGAUGUGAGGCUGAGUGUGUUUAAGUACGUGAGAGAGUGUGAGUGUGUUUGUAAGUGAGUGUCCCUAUGCGAUUAUGUCUCUUUACGUUGCUAAGGGGGGAGGGUGAGGAUUAAGUACUCGUGCCUUAUAUUUGUGUGCCAAUUAAUGCCUAAUAAAUACCAUGUGCUUAAACAAGUACAAGGAAGUUGAACACCCA